AGCCCUUUCCCAGGCGGUAGCGGGGGCAGUGGUGCUGUUGCCCUUUUAAACUGCGGCUUGACGGGAGCCGCGCCUCCUGUCGGUGGAGUCGGUUAUAAAGGGAGCAGCCCCGCAGGCCGCCACAUAGCUCCCGCCAAGUCCUCGGUGCCCCUUGCCAUUUUCCAGCCGCGCUCCCACGAGGGUCACGGCGGCGGGGAGAGGUGGAGCCGCGAGAGCUCGGCCGGGGGCCCCGCCUGGUGGUCGCGGCCAUGACAGCGGCUCGGGACAGGCUCCUUUUCCGCGCCCCUCCCGCCGGAGGUGAGGGGAAGAUGUCCAUGUCCGGGUUCAAGGCCAAACCGAAGUUACUGGCCUCUAUCUUCCAGGAGAACCAGGAGCCACAGCCGCGGCUCACGCCCCACCGCAACAUUAAGAUUACAAGUGGACACCUGAGUCAGCAGGACCUGGAAUCCCAGAUGAGAGAGCUUAUCUACACGACUCAGAUCUUGUUGUCACCCCCAUUAUUGACAAUCCAAAGGUGCAGAAAGCACUCUGACAAAUAAUGAAACAACCACCAUCGGUUAAAUUUGAUGCAAAAAUAUUGCAUCUACCAGCAUUUUCAGUUAUAAUUUCUGAAAGACCAAGAUUGGAAUGACUUUUUGUAACAAGUGUGCUCGCAGAUCGACUCCAGUGAGAAGAGCUCGGGGACCUCCUGAGCCAAGCUUAAUCUCCUUUGCUGUUUGUGAGUGGUGGCUGGUCACCAGGAGGUGGCCACCAGGCUCCUCCUUUCCCCGCUGUUCCAAUUGCUAAUCCAGCAUUUGUGGAUAGCUGCAAACUGCGAUAUUGCUGAUGAGCGCUUUGACGCCACAUUCCACACUAACGUGUUGGUGAAUUCUUCUGGGCAUUGCCAGUACCUGCCUCCAGGCAUAUUCAAGAGUUCCUGCUACAUCGAUGUACGCUGGUUUCCCUUUGAUGUGCAGCACUGCAAACUGAAGUUUGGGUCCUGGUCUUACGGAGGCUGGUCCUUGGAUCUGCAGAUGCAGGAGGCAGAUAUCAGUGGCUAUAUCCCCAAUGGAGAAUGGGACCUAGUGGGAAUCCCCGGCAAGAGGAGUGAAAGGUUCUAUGAGUGCUGCAAAGAGCCCUACCCUGAUGUCACCUUCACAGUGACCAUGCGCCGCAGGACGCUCUACUAUGGCCUCAACCUGCUGAUCCCCUGUGUGCUCAUCUCCGCCCUCGCCCUGCUGGUGUUCCUGCUUCCUGCAGAUUCCGGGGAGAAGAUUUCCCUGGGGAUAACAGUCUUACUCUCUCUUACCGUCUUCAUGCUGCUCGUGGCUGAGAUCAUGCCCGCAACAUCCGAUUCGGUACCAUUGAUAGCCCAGUACUUCGCCAGCACCAUGAUCAUCGUGGGCCUCUCGGUGGUGGUGACGGUGAUCGUGCUGCAGUACCACCACCACGACCCCGACGGGGGCAAGAUGCCCAAGUGGACCAGAGUCAUCCUUCUGAACUGGUGCGCGUGGUUCCUGCGAAUGAAGAGGCCCGGGGAGGACAAGGUGCGCCCGGCCUGCCAGCACAAGCAGCGGCGCUGCAGCCUGGCCAGUGUGGAGAUGAGUGCCGUGGCGCCGCCGCCCGCCAGCAACGGGAACCUGCUGUACAUCGGCUUCCGCGGCCUGGACGGCGUGCACUGUGUCCCGACCCCCGACUCUGGGGUAGUGUGUGGCCGCAUGGCCUGCUCCCCCACGCACGAUGAGCACCUCCUGCACGGCGGGCAACCCCCCGAGGGGGACCCGGACUUGGCCAAGAUCCUGGAGGAGGUCCGCUACAUUGCCAACCGCUUCCGCUGCCAGGACGAAAGCGAGGCGGUCUGCAGCGAGUGGAAGUUCGCCGCCUGUGUGGUGGACCGCCUGUGCCUCAUGGCCUUCUCGGUCUUCACCAUCAUCUGCACCAUCGGCAUCCUGAUGUCGGCUCCCAACUUCGUGGAGGCCGUGUCCAAAGACUUUGCGUAACCACGCCUGGUUCUGUACAUGUGGAAAACUCACAGAUGGGCAAGGCCUUUGGCUUGGCGAGAUUUGGGGGUGCUAAUCCAGGACAGCAUUACACGCCACAACUCCAGUGUUCCCUUCUGGCUGUCAGUCGUGUUGCUUACGGUUUCUUUGUUACUUUAGGUAGUAGAAUCUCAGCACUUUGUUUCAUAUUCUCAGAUGGGCUGAUAGAUAUCCUUGGCACAUCCGUACCAUCGGUCAGCAGGGCCACUGAGUAGUCAUUUUGCCCAUUAGCCCACUGCCUGGAAAGCCCUUCGGAGAGCUCCCCAUGGCUCCUCACCACCGAGACAGUUGGUUUUGCAUGUCUGCAUGAAGGUCUACCUGAAAAUUCAACAUUUGCUUUUUGCUUGUGUACAAACCCAGAUUGAAGCUAAAAUAAACCAGACUCACUAAAUCCUUUCCAAUAAUUGACUGGUGGAAGGAAAACAAAAAACAAAAACUAAAAACCUCUUAGCUUUUCUGCAAUUCAACUUUUUAUUUUUAUUUUUAUUUCUAUCAAAGACGGUAGAGAGAAACAGCUUGAUGCUGUUUCUACAUCAAAAAAAAAAAAAAAAAAGACAGACUGUUGGUCUUACUAAGGAUGUUUUUACCAGCCUGCCUGACUUCUGCAAACCUACCCUGUCAAGGAGAUCAAAGGGACGCAGGUUUCUGUUUAUUCUGAACAAGGGCCAGGCCCCGCGGAGUGUCUUUGGUGGAUCCCAGAUAACUCCUAGGUGCUGCUCUCAGACACUGAGGAGUUGAGCAAAUCUGUUCUAUUCUGCAGAACCCAUAGGACAAAUAAGAGUUCUACUAGAAUUAACAGCCCAAAAGAAUAGCUACAGCUAAGUGAAGCCACUUACGUGGGCUUUAAAAAAAUAAUGUGUUAGCUGAUUCACAUGCACUGGAGUUAAUUAGUCUUAGAAAUGUGUGCAUCCAUACAAAUGCACAACAUAAAGUGAACAUAUUCCUAGGCCCUUUCUGCCUGUGUCAGGGCCAGGAAGUAGAGGCUGGGAACUCUUCUGGUCCCCAGUAUGGCAGGCGCCAGGGAGGGGAUGGUGUGGCCCAUCCCUUCUCUGGAUACCUGGCCAGUGGCAGGCAGCAGGGAGGAGCUGGCCGACCCUCAGUGACUGACAAGCCAGCAAUUCUGAGUUCUGGCCUUUGGGAGUCUGCCUGCUCCAAGCCAGUCCACCCCAGCUGCAGCCCCAAAAGCUGGCUCAAAGUCCUUGGGUGGAUUCACUGGAGAUGGGCAACUUAAAACAAGAGAAACUUUAAUUUUUAAACCUAAGUGAUGAUACAGCUCUUCCCUUAGAUUAUCGCCCAGGCUGGAGUGCAGUGGCAUGAUCUCAGCUCACUGCAAGCUCCACCUCCUGGGUUCAUGCCAUUCUCCUGCCUCAGCCUCCCCCCGAGUAACUGGGAAUACAGGCGCCCGCCACCAUGCCUGGCUAAUUUUUUGUAUUUUUAGUAGAGAUAGGGUUUCAUCAUGUUAGCCAGGAUGGUCUCAUUCUUAUUCUUUAAUGAGAUCAGAGGGUAAUUCACCAAGAAAGACCUCUCCUGUUCCAUUGUGUCAUCCAACAACUGCUCAGAGCUCAAAAUUAUAGAAGGCUUCUGAGCCCCUAGAGAUUUUUAAUUUGCUUCUAAUCCCUGAGGUGGGAACAUCAUGAGGGAAGAUUUGAUUUUCAGAGUUAAAUAAAUUGUAUGUGCUUUUCCAGCCA